AGGGGUUGCCGGAUCCCGUCCGCGGGCGAUGCUGCUGCGGAGGGUGGUCGAGGGAGGCCGGGCGGUAGCCGCCGCGGUCCGUGGCUCGGCAAGUACCAGGACGGGUCUUGGCAGCGCCGAAGGGCACGUCCGAGAGGCCGCUGUCCGGGGGCCCGCACGUACCGGGAGGAGCCCCGGCCCCUCCACCCGCAUGUGGGGACGGAGCCGGGAGGAUCGCGCGCUGGCCGCCGCCGAAGGACCCCUCGCUCCUCUCCUCCAUCGGCUCUUACCGAGUCCCCGCCCCGGAAUCUGUGGAGGGGCCGCUUAGCCUUGGGAGAGGAAGCAGCCCGGUGAACGGCCACUUUCCUGUUUCUCAGUAUCUGCCGAGCGCCUGUGUGCGAGCCCUCCUGGGCUCUGGGGACUGGCCGUGGACAUGGAGCGGAUGAUGCCCCUCGCAGGACUAGUUAAAUAAGUGAAGUUGGUAGCGUGUCAGUCCGUGAUCCUGGGUAGAUAGAGCAGGGCAGCGACGGAAGACUGCCUAUAGGACAUUCACGCUGGGAUGAGAGGGGCCUGAGAGGCCUGGGCUUUGUGACAGGGAAACUUGGAUAAAGGGUGGUGCGAUUCUUCCGGUUGGUCCCUCAGAGGUGGUGGGGCUUGGUUAUACUGGUAGAGGUGCUGGGCUGGCCAGGAGCUUACAGGGUUACACCUCUCGCAUACUGGUGUCCACAGAGCAGCCAUCUUAGCUGGAGGUGUCGAGUGCCUCCCCCACCCCCCACCAUGUGCUUGAGUGCACACCCGGCGCCAGGCCCUGAUCCUGGCACUUCUUGUGAAUCACACCGUGUCAUACCCAUGACUUCCAUUGCACAGUGGGGAAACUGAGUCUAGAGAGGUGAAAUAACAUGUCUAAAGUCACAGGAAGUGAAAAAGCUGAGGACAUGGAGCCAGUUGCCCAAUGACAGGAGAGCUGAAAUGUCCUCACUGCUGGGGGUAGACCGGGCCUCACCAGCUUCCUGGAGAGUCACAUGUUUGUCUGCAUCCUCAGGGGGCUCGCCGGUUCUCCAGCCCGGACUGCUGCCAGAGGCUUCCUGGAGGUGGCAGCUUUCUUCAAAGGCACCAUCCCGGAGCGCAAGCCCCUGAUGGGCGCAGAAAAUUCGGGACAGACCACGUAGAGGUGGGCUCCCAAGCAGGUGCGGACGGCACCAGGCCGCCCAAGGCAUCGCUGCCACCUGAGCUCCAGCCGCCCACAAACUGCUGCAUGAGUGGCUGCCCCAACUGCGUGUGGGUGGAGUACGCGGACAGGCUGCUGCAGCACUUCCAGGACGGUGGGGAGCGGGCCCUGGCUGCCCUGGAGGAGCACGUGGCUGAUGAGAACCUCAAGGCCUUCCUCAGGAUGGAGAUCCGGCUGCACACCAGGUGCGGAGGCUGAGCCAUCCCUGCUGGACUCCCUACCGCAGGACGGAGUCCAGGACGCAGCCGCAGCCUCCUUCCUUCACACCCCCUCACAGACUCCUUGUGUCCAACGGGAAUAGGAAGAAUUAGUUACUGACUUCACCUGAGAAAAAAAUAAAUUCUCUAUGGUGGUUUCACAGGA